AGUGUCUUCAGCAGCAGGGUAAUUGCUGCCGGGCCACUUGCUGAGGAAGUGCUUGGAACUGAUUUGAAAUCACAGAAAACAGUGAGCAUUCUUUGUGGUUAACGAUGUGCUUCUUUUAAGCACACCCCAGCCAACGGCGACAAAGAAAUGUUUGGAAAGCAAAUUGAAAGGCUGUAAGGGAGAGAUGAAGAGAGUGUGCAACCCUGACACAGCUCAGCUGGUGCUUUGUUAAGAGAUAUUUAUAAGUCUUCAGAUUAUGCCCCCCAAUUUCCAGGCAACGAAGAGACUUCUCCAAGUGUCGUGCUUUGUGCAUUAGUAAUAAGGACACAUGCUCCACAGUAAUGCUGGAACACAGGAUGAUGCUCUUCAGCUGUGUGCUUCUUCCUGGCGGAGCAGAUGAUUUCAUAAUUAGCCUGAGGAAACAGGCAGACCUAACAGCCAAGGAAACAAUGCACCUGAAUUGACAAACGAAGUUCAAGGCUUUAGGCAACCAAUGGCAUAUUUCUAGAGUGUUGGAAGGAGAGGCAAGAGUCUACUUCAAAGAAACUGAAUGGAUUAUUUUACAAAUGCAAAUAGAGAGUUGAAAAAAGAUGCUCAGCAAGAUUACCAUCUAGAAUAUGCCAUGGAAAAUAGCACACACACAAUAAUUGAAUUUACCAGAGAGCUGCAUACAUGUGACAUAAAUGACAAGAGUAUAACGGAUAGCACUGUGAGAGUGAUCUGGGCCUACCACCAUGAAGAUGCAGGAGAAGCUGGUCCCAAGUACCAUGACUCCAAUAGGGGCACCAAGAGUUUGCGGUUAUUGAAUCCUGAGAAAACUAGUGUGCUAUCUACAGCCUUACCAUACUUUGAUCUGGUAAAUCAGGACGUCCCCAUCCCAAACAAAGAUACAACAUAUUGGUGCCAAAUGUUUAAGAUUCCUGUGUUCCAAGAAAAGCAUCAUGUAAUAAAGGUUGAGCCAGUGAUACAGAGAGGCCAUGAGAGUCUGGUGCACCACAUCCUGCUCUAUCAGUGCAGCAACAACUUUAACGACAGCGUUCUGGAGUCCGGCCACGAGUGCUAUCACCCCAACAUGCCCGAUGCAUUCCUCACCUGUGAAACUGUGAUUUUUGCCUGGGCUAUUGGUGGAGAGGGCUUUUCUUAUCCACCUCAUGUUGGAUUAUCCCUUGGCACUCCAUUAGAUCCGCAUUAUGUGCUCCUAGAAGUCCAUUAUGAUAAUCCCACUUAUGAGGAAGGCUUAAUAGAUAAUUCUGGACUGAGGUUAUUUUACACAAUGGAUAUAAGGAAAUAUGAUGCUGGGGUGAUUGAGGCUGGCCUCUGGGUGAGCCUCUUCCAUACCAUCCCUCCAGGGAUGCCUGAGUUCCAGUCUGAGGGUCACUGCACUUUGGAGUGCCUGGAAGAGGCUCUGGAAGCCGAAAAGCCAAGUGGAAUUCAUGUGUUUGCUGUUCUUCUCCAUGCUCACCUGGCUGGCAGAGGCAUCAGGCUGCGUCAUUUUCGAAAAGGGAAGGAAAUGAAAUUACUUGCCUAUGAUGAUGAUUUUGACUUCAAUUUCCAGGAGUUUCAGUAUCUAAAGGAAGAACAAACAAUCUUACCAGGAGAUAACCUAAUUACUGAGUGUCGCUACAACACGAAAGAUAGAGCUGAGAUGACUUGGGGAGGACUAAGCACCAGGAGUGAAAUGUGUCUCUCAUACCUUCUUUAUUACCCAAGAAUUAAUCUUACUCGAUGUGCAAGUAUUCCAGACAUUAUGGAACAACUUCAGUUCAUUGGGGUUAAGGAGAUCUACAGACCAGUCACGACCUGGCCUUUCAUUAUCAAAAGUCCCAAGCAAUAUAAAAACCUUUCUUUCAUGGAUGCUAUGAAUAAGUUUAAAUGGACUAAAAAGGAAGGUCUCUCCUUCAACAAGCUGGUCCUCAGCCUGCCAGUGAAUGUGAGAUGUUCCAAGACAGACAAUGCUGAGUGGUCGAUUCAAGGAAUGACAGCAUUACCUCCAGAUAUAGAAAGACCCUAUAAAGCAGAACCUUUGGUGUGUGGCACGUCUUCUUCCUCUUCCCUGCACAGAGAUUUCUCCAUCAACUUGCUUGUUUGCCUUCUGCUACUCAGCUGCACGCUGAGCACCAAGAGCUUGUGAUCAAAAUUCUGUUGGACUUGACAAUGUUUUCUAUGAUCUGAACCUGUCAUUUGAAGUACAGGUUAAAGACUGUGUCCACUUUGGGCAUGAAGAGUGUGGAGACUUUUCUUCCCCAUUUUCCCUCCCUCCUUUUUCCUUUCCAUGUUACAUGAGAGACAUCAAUCAGGUUCUCUUCUCUUUCUUAGAAAUAUCUGAUGUUAUAUAUACAUGGUCAAUAAAAUAAAACUGGCCUGACUUAAGAUAACCAUUUUAAAAAAUUGGGCUGUCAUGUGGGAAUAAAAGAAUUCUUUCUUUCCUACUACAUUCUGUUUUAUUUAAAUACUCAUUGUUGCUAUUUCACUUUUUGACUUGACUUUUAUAUUUCUUUAAAAAAUUCCUUCCUUUUAAAAAAUAUAAAAGGGACUACUGUUCAUUCCAGUUUUCUUCUUCUUUGUUGUUCUUCUAGUGUGACUUUUCAAGUGUAACAGCCAUUCUUCCUGACUUUAAUAUUGUCCAGUUCUGGUCUUUUCUGUGAAUUACCACUGGGCCCCUUACCUCAAUGCUUUUUGUUGAUGCCCACUCUGGUUCCCUUGUUUAUCUGAGUCUGUUGGUACCCCAAAUGACCCCACACCCAUCUUAAAGUACUUUUUUUCACCUUCCCUGUUUAGUACUGGCCAGAUGAGUUUUUUCUAGAGCUCUGUCACUAUCUGAAAAGAAAGAGGCUAUGGGAAACAUAGAAAUGGUAUGUAUUAAUAACUGAUCAUAGGCUGAGGAGAAAAAAUGUAGCUGGCUGCAAACCCAGUGCUGUGAGGUGACUUAUAUGAGGUUCCAGAUCAAAGACAGGCCGUGUGAGCCAGUCCAGGAGGGUGUAAGUUCUGAAUGGUUCCUUGCUGACUUUGGGUGACACAUGUACCACAUACUGGCUCAGUUUAAGUCAUGGUUCUAUUGUAGAUUUAUUUUUAUAUUAGUUAAUAAAUGACUUUAAAUUGUCACCAAUUGAAAAUCUUGUCACUCUUUUGGUUUUCUUUAUAUAGCUCAGCCAAAUCUUGUUUUAUGUCCUGUCCUCAUCUCUUAAGCUAAAUCUGUUUGGAUCAUAUUAAUAAACUAAAUGAAAUUACA